GUGCUUCCAGCGGACGGCAGCGCGCGAGGUGAGACGGCGAGGGCUCCCGGGGCGCAGGUAGAGAUGUUCCGUCGGUGCCGAAGGCCCGGCUAGUGCGGUUGUGUGGACGGCGAAAAAAGCAAGUCCGCCUUCACAAGUCCCAUGGGGCUGGGGAGAGGGUGGGAGGCGGAGAGGGUAUGGGGAGGGGAGACUCUCCUCAGAUCCUCUCGACACCGUCGGGUCUGGGCUCCAAGUCCAAGGCCAUCGAUCACCUGCCACCCACAGACCAGGCCAGGCGUCAAAGCAAGUCACCCAUCCGACCUAAACCCCUCUAAGACCCCGGAGUCACGUCUCCCUCCGGGGAUCCUCGUGAGGUCUUGGGGGUCCCACCGCCCUGCGAGCCGCGCCCGCGCCCCGCCAGACCCGGAACUGCGUCGCUAGCCCUUCUCUGUACCAGGCCGGGAGAGGGAGGCGGCGCCGCAGAGCCUCGGGUGCAGUCUGAGAAGUUUGGGAGUGACUUGAAGAGUGACUGGAAGCACCCCAGACCCGGUUUGUCCGGUCACAGCCGGGUCCUUACGUGAGUUAGGAGAGGAGUGGGGGUCGGACGGGAGCCCCACUGAGAGUAAGGGCGCGCGUUUGUUCACAGAACGUCGGGACCUGGUUCCCUCUUUAAUCACACCCCCGGGGGCGCUUCGUGUGAGGUUCCACGGGGGAAGGCGAGAGGCGCAGGCUGCCACACACGCACUGUUUGGAAGAGGGGAAGCAUUGCCCCCCCUGCACCACCUCACCAAGAUGGCUACUUUGGGACACACAUUCCCCUUCUAUGCUGGCCCCAAGCCAACCUUCCCGAUGGACACCACUUUGGCCAGCAUCAUCAUGAUCUUUCUGACUGCACUGGCCACGUUCAUCGUCAUCCUGCCUGGCAUUCGGGGAAAGACGAGGCUGUUCUGGCUGCUUCGGGUGGUGACCAGCUUAUUCAUCGGGGCUGCAAUCCUGGCUGUGAAUUUCAGUUCUGAGUGGUCUGUGGGCCAGGUCAGCACCAACACAUCAUACAAGGCCUUCAGUUCUGAGUGGAUCAGCGCUGAUAUUGGGCUGCAGGUCGGGCUGGGUGGAGUCAACAUCACACUCACAGGGACCCCCGUGCAGCAGCUGAAUGAGACCAUCAAUUACAACGAGGAGUUCACCUGGCGCCUGGGUGAGAACUAUGCUGAGGAGUAUGCAAAGGCUCUGGAGAAGGGGCUGCCAGACCCUGUGUUGUACCUAGCUGAGAAGUUCACUCCAAGAAGCCCAUGUGGCCUAUACCGCCAGUACCGCCUGGCGGGACACUACACCUCAGCCAUGCUAUGGGUGGCAUUCCUCUGCUGGCUGCUGGCCAAUGUGAUGCUCUCCAUGCCUGUGCUGGUAUAUGGUGGCUACAUGCUAUUGGCCACGGGCAUCUUCCAGCUGUUGGCUCUGCUCUUCUUCUCCAUGGCCACAUCACUCACCUCACCCUGUCCCCUGCACCUGGGCGCUUCUGUGCUGCAUACUCACCAUGGGCCUGCCUUCUGGAUCACAUUGACCACAGGACUGCUGUGUGUGCUGCUGGGCCUGGCUAUGGCGGUGGCCCACAGGAUGCAGCCUCACAGGCUGAAGGCUUUCUUCAACCAGAGUGUGGAUGAAGACCCCAUGCUGGAGUGGAGUCCUGAGGAAGGUGGACUCCUGAGCCCCCGCUACCGGUCCAUGGCUGACAGUCCCAAGUCCCAGGACAUUCCCCUGUCAGAGGCUUCCUCCACCAAGGCAUACUGUAAGGAGGCACACCCCAAAGAUCCUGAUUGUGCUUUAUAACAUUCCUCCCCGUGGAGGCCACCUGGACUUCCAGUCUGGCUCCAAACCUCAUUGGCGCCCCAUAAAACCAGCAGAACUGCCCUCAGGGUGGCUGUUACCAGACACCCAGCACCAAUCUACAGACGGAGUAGAAAAAGGAGGCUCUAUAUACUGAUGUUAAAAAACAAAACAAAACAAAAAGCCCUAAGGGACUGAAGAGAUGCUGGGCCUGUCCAUAAAGCCUGUUGCCAUGAUAAGGCCAAGCAGGGGCUAGCUUAUCUGCACAGCAACCCAGCCUUUCCGUGCUGCCUUGCCUCUUCAAGAUGCUAUUCACUGAAACCUAACUUCACCCCCAUAACACCAGCAGGGUGGGGGUUACAUAUGAUUCUCCUAUGGUUUCCUCUCAUCCCUCGGCACCUCUUGUUUUCCUUUUUCCUGGGUUCCUUUUGUUCUUCCUUUACUUCUCCAGCUUGUGUGGCCUUUUGGUACAAUGAAAGACAGCACUGGAAAGGAGGGGAAACCAAACUUCUCAUCCUAGGUCUAACAUUAACCAACUAUGCCACAUUCUCUUUGAGCUUCAGUUCCCAAAUUUGCUACAUAAGAUUGCAAGACUUGCCAAGAAUCUUGGGAUUUAUCUUUCUAUGCCUUGCUGACACCUACCUUGGCCCUCAAACACCACCUCACAAGAAGCCAGGUGGGAAGUUAGGGAAUCAACUCCAAAACGCUAUUCCUUCCCACCCCACUCAGCUGGGCUAGCUGAGUGGCAUCCAGGACGGGGGAGUGGGUGACCUGCCUCAUCACUGCCACCUAACGUCCCCCUGGGGUGGUUCAGAAAGAUGCUAGCUCUGGUAGGGUCCCUCCGGCCUCACUAGAGGGCGCCCCUAUUACUCUGGAGUCGACGCAGAGAAUCAGGUUUCACAGCACUGCGGAGAGUGUACUAGGCUGUCUCCAGCCCAGCGAAGCUCAUGAGGACGUGCGACCCCGGCGCGGAGAAGCCAUGAAAAUUAAUGGGAAAAACAGUUUUUAAAAAACAAAAGAAAAAAAGGUUUAUUUACAGAUCGCCCCAGGAGACUUUCCCUGGUGCCUGCGGAUGUCCGAGGCCUCGCGCCAGCAGCGCUCAGUGCCCUUCCUGGAGCUCUCCUGGCCCAGGCCUGGCGGGCACUGCUUCCCGGCCUGCGAUGUCCCAAGGCGGGGAAGGAGUCCAGAUUGGGUCCCCCUCACAGGUUAGUGGUGAUACAUUUUAAGUCUGGGAGAGCGGCCUGCUUGUGCAGUGGGUCGCCGAGGAUAAGAGGUGAGCCCCCUCUCUCCUGGCUGCAGUCCUUGGCGCUUUGGUCCAGAAGGGUGCGAAGAGCGCUGGGCCGAACAUACUGGAGACUCACCACGGCCCCUCCGAGGAAGAGGCACAGGACGCCUGUGGCGGUGGGGAUCGAAAGAAAGGAGGGCAUGUGGAGUCAGGGCUAUGUUGCCCAGGCUGGUCUCGAACUCUGGCCUCAAACGACCUUCCUGCCUCGACCUCCCAAAGUGCUGGGAUUACAGGCGUGAUGCCCGGGCCUUCUUCCAUCUUUUGGAGCCUACCCCUUGUGUUACCUCCCGCCACACACCUCUAAUCUGAAUUACAUGAAACACGGCAAGACACCAAACCCUUCUGAGCCCCCCACUUUUCAUCUGUAAAAUGGUCAUAACAGUGCCUGUUUCUGCGAACUAUUGAGAGGGGCAAAUAGGGUAAUAGAUGUGAAUUCAUUCUGUAAACUGGAAAGUGCA